AUCUGAACUGAUGUCACAGCAUCAUGCAGCAGGUCAAACAAGGCAUCUCCUAGUAUUGCAUCCUACAGAUGUGCUGUAAACAUCAAAAGAAGACGGUGGGAUCAGGAGAUGAGAGCACUGGACUGGGAGUAAGGCACCUGAAUUUUUAGUCCCUGCUGACAUACUCUUCCUGAAUCUUGGUUUCCUCCACAGUAAAACAAAAGGUUCCGGAAGCUGGGAAGUCCAAGGUCAAGGUACCAAAGAUUUGGUGUCAGGUAUUGAAUGUGUAAGCAGACACAGGGGUAACUCUCAAGGAACAAAAUUGCCUGAAGGCUUUUCCACAGCUGUUUUGGAAAGAAGUGAGGUUUAGACUUCUCCAUGUUAACCAUGAGCGUGACACUUUCCCCCCUGAGGUCACAGGACCUGGAUCCCAUGGCUACUGAUGCUUCACCCAUGGCCAUCAACAUGACACCCACUGUGGAGCAGGGUGAGGGAGAAGAGGCAAUGAAGGACAUGGACUCUGACCAGCAGUAUGAAAAGCCACCCCCACUACACACAGGGGCUGACUGGAAGAUUGUCCUCCACUUACCUGAAAUUGAGACCUGGCUCCGGAUGACCUCAGAGAGGGUCCGAGACCUAACCUAUUCAGUCCAGCAGGAUUCGGACAGCAAGCAUGUGGAUGUACAUCUAGUUCAACUAAAGGACAUUUGUGAAGAUAUUUCUGAUCAUGUUGAGCAAAUCCAUGCCCUCCUUGAAACAGAGUUCUCCCUAAAGCUGCUGUCUUACUCUGUCAACGUGAUAGUGGACAUCCACGCAGUGCAGCUCCUCUGGCACCAGCUUCGAGUCUCAGUGCUGGUUCUGCGGGAGCGCAUUCUGCAAGGUCUGCAGGACGCCAAUGGCAACUACACUAGGCAGACGGACAUUCUGCAAGCUUUCUCUGAAGAGACAAAAGAGGGCCGGCUUGAUUCUCUAACAGAAGUGGAUGACUCAGGACAAUUAACCAUCAAAUGUUCUCAAAAUUACUUGUCUCUGGAUUGUGGCAUUACUGCAUUCGAACUGUCUGACUACAGUCCAAGUGAGGAUUUGCUCAGUGGGCUAGGUGACAUGACCUCUAGCCAAGUCAAAACCAAACCCUUUGACUCUUGGAGCUACAGUGAGAUGGAAAAGGAGUUUCCUGAGCUUAUCCGAAGUGUUGGUUUACUUACGGUAGCUGCUGACUCUAUCUCUACCAAUGGCAGUGAAGCAGUUACUGAGGAGGUAUCUCAAGUAUCUCUCUCAGUAGACGACAAAGGUGGAUGUGAGGAAGACAAUGCUUCUGCAGUCGAAGAGCAACCAGGCUUAACACUGGGGGUGUCAUCAUCUUCAGGAGAAGCUCUGACAAAUGCUGCUCAACCCUCCUCUGAGACUGUGCAGCAAGAAUCCAGUUCCUCCUCCCAUCAUGAUGCAAAGAAUCAGCAGCCUGUUCCUUGUGAAAAUGCAACCCCCAAACGAACCAUCAGAGAUUGCUUUAAUUAUAACGAGGACUCUCCCACGCAGCCUACAUUGCCAAAAAGAGGACUUUUUCUUAAAGAGGAAACUUUUAAGAAUGAUCUGAAAGGCAAUGGUGGAAAGAGGCAAAUGGUUGAUCUAAAGCCUGAGAUGAGCAGAAGCACCCCUUCGCUAGUAGAUCCUCCUGACAGAUCCAAACUUUGCCUGGUAUUGCAGUCUUCUUACCCCAACAGCCCUUCUGCUGCCAGCCAGUCUUAUGAGUGUUUACACAAGGUGGGGAAUGGGAACCUUGAAAACACAGUCAAAUUUCACAUUAAAGAAAUUUCUUCCAGCCUGGGAAGGCUUAACGACUGCUAUAAAGAGAAAUCUCGACUUAAAAAGCCACACAAGACCUCAGAAGAGGUGCCUCCAUGCCGAACACCUAAACGGGGGACUGGUUCAGGCAAACAAGCUAAAAAUACAAAGAGCUCAGCAGUGCCAAAUGGAGAGCUUUCUUAUACUUCCAAGGCCAUAGAGGGGCCACAAACAAAUUCUGCUUCCACAUCCUCACUUGAGCCUUGUAAUCAGAGAAGUUGGAAUGCCAAAUUGCAAUUGCAGUCAGAAACAUCCAGUUCACCAGCUUUUACUCAGAGCAGUGAAUCCUCUGUUGGCUCAGACAACAUCAUGUCUCCGGUGCCACUUCUUUCAAAACACAAAAGCAAAAAAGGUCAAGCCUCCUCUCCAAGUCACGUCACUAGGAAUGGUGAGGUUGUGGAGGCCUGGUAUGGCUCUGAUGAAUACCUAGCACUGCCCUCUCACCUUAAGCAGACAGAAGUAUUGGCUUUGAAGUUGGAAAACCUAACAAAGCUUCUGCCUCAGAAACCCAGAGGAGAAACCAUCCAGAAUAUUGAUGACUGGGAACUGUCUGAAAUGAAUUCAGAUUCUGAAAUCUAUCCAACCUAUCAUGUCAAAAAGAAGCAUACAAGGCUAGGCAGGGUGUCUCCAAGCUCAUCUAGUGACAUAGCCUCUUCACUAGGGGAGAGCAUUGAAUCUGGGCCCCUGAGUGACAUUCUUUCUGAUGAGGAGUCCAGUAUGCCUCUCGCUGGCAUGAAAAAGUAUGCUGAUGAGAAGUCAGAAAGAGCUUCAUCCUCUGAGAAAAAUGAGAGCCAUUCUGCCACUAAAUCAGCUUUAAUUCAGAAACUGAUGCAAGAUAUUCAGCACCAAGACAACUAUGAAGCCAUAUGGGAAAAAAUAGAGGGGUUUGUAAACAAACUGGAUGAAUUCAUUCAAUGGUUAAAUGAAGCCAUGGAAACUACAGAAAAUUGGACUCCCCCUAAAGCAGAGAUGGAUGACCUUAAACUGUAUCUGGAGACACACUUGAGUUUUAAGUUGAAUGUAGACAGUCAUUGUGCUCUCAAGGAAGCUGUGGAGGAGGAAGGACACCAACUUCUUGAGCUUAUUGCAUCUCACAAAGCAGGACUGAAGGACAUGCUGCGGAUGAUUGCAAGUCAAUGGAAGGAGCUGCAGAGGCAAAUCAAACGGCAGCACAGCUGGAUUCUCAGGGCUCUGGAUACCAUCAAAGCCGAGAUACUGGCUACUGAUGUGUCUGUGGAGGAUGAGGAAGGGACUGGAAGCCCCAAGGCUGAGGUUCAACUAUGCUACCUGGAAGCACAAAGAGAUGCUGUUGAGCAGAUGUCCCUCAAGCUGUACAGCGAGCAGUAUACCAGCAGCAGCAAGCGAAAGGAAGAGUUUGCUGAUAUGUCAAAAGUUCAUUCAGUGGGAAGCAAUGGGCUUCUGGACUUUGAUUCAGAAUAUCAGGAGCUCUGGGAUUGGCUGAUUGACAUGGAGUCCCUUGUGAUGGACAGCCACGACCUGAUGAUGUCAGAGGAGCAGCAGCAGCAUCUUUACAAGCGAUACAGUGUGGAAAUGUCCAUCAGACACCUGAAAAAGACGGAGCUGCUUAGUAAGGUUGAAGCUUUGAAGAAAGGUGGCGUUUUACUACCAAAUGAUCUCCUUGAAAAAGUGGAUUCAAUUAAUGAAAAAUGGGAACUGCUUGGGAAAACCCUAGGAGAGAAGAUCCAGGACACAAUGGCAGGGCACAGUGGGUCGAGUCCACGUGACCUGCUCUCUCCUGAAAGUGGAAGCCUGGUAAGGCAGCUGGAGGUCAGGAUCAAAGAACUGAAAGGAUGGCUAAGAGAUACAGAGCUUUUCAUCUUCAAUUCCUGUCUGAGACAAGAAAAGGAAGGAACAAUGAAUACUGAGAAACAACUGCAAUACUUUAAGUCCCUCUGUCGUGAAAUCAAGCAACGACGUCGAGGAGUUGCCUCCAUUCUGCGACUAUGCCAGCAUCUUUUGGAUGACCGGGAGACUUGCAAUCUGAAUGCAGACCACCAGCCCAUGCAGCUGAUCAUUGUAAAUCUUGAAAGAAGGUGGGAAGCCAUUGUCAUGCAAGCCGUCCAGUGGCAAACACGUCUACAAAAGAAGAUGGGAAAGGAAUCUGAGACUUUGAAUGUGAUUGAUCCUGGCUUGAUGGACCUAAAUGGGAUGAGUGAGGAUGCCCUGGAAUGGGAUGAAAUGGACAUAAGUAACAAGUUAAUUAGUUUGAAUGAGGAAUCAAAUGACCUUGAUCAAGAACUCCAACCUGUUAUCCCUUCCUUGAAGCUUGGAGAGACAAGUAAUGAGGACCCUGGUUAUGACGAGGAGGCUGAUAACCAUGGGGGAUCUCAGUAUGCCUCAAAUAUUACUGCCCCCUCUAGUCCACACAUUUACCAGGUGUACAGCCUCCACAAUGUUGAACUCUAUGAGGACAACCACAUGCCAUUUCUGAAAAACAAUCCAAAGGUCACUGGCAUGACACAGCCUAAUGUUUUAACUAAGAGUCUCAGUAAAGACUCUUCAUUUUCAUCUACCAAAUCUUUGCCAGAUCUUCUAGGUGGUUCCAAUUUGGUAAAGCCCUGCGCAUGUCAUGGAGGAGACAUGAGCCAGAAUUCAGGCAGUGAGAGUGGAAUUGUCAGUGAAGGAGACACAGAAACCACUACCAACUCUGAAAUGUGCUUGCUCAAUGCAGUGGAUGGGUCCCCAAGUAACCUUGAAACUGAACAUCUGGACCCACAAAUGGGAGAUGCAGUUAACGUGUUAAAGCAAAAAUUUACAGAUGAGGGGGAAAGCAUUAAGCUUCCAAAUAGCUCUCAGUCGUCCAUUUCACCAGUGGGUUGUGUAAAUGGAAAAGUUGGAGAUUUAAACAGUAUUACCAAACAUACCCCUGACUGUUUGGGAGAAGAAUUACAAGGAAAACAUGAUGUGUUUACAUUUUAUGAUUACUCAUACCUCCAAGGCUCAAAACUCAAAUUACCAAUGAUAAUGAAACAGUCACAAAGCGAAAAAGCGCAUGUGGAGGAUCCCCUGCUUCGUGGUUUUUAUUUUGAUAAAAAAUCAUGCAAAUCUAAACAUCAGACUACAGAGUUACAACCAGAUGUACCUCCCCAUGAAAGGAUUUUGGCAAGUGCAUCUCAUGAAAUGGAUCGCAUUUCAUAUAAAAGUGGCAAUAUAGAAAAGACAUUCACUGGCAUGCAGAAUGCCAAACAGCUCUCCCUUUUAUCUCAUAGUUCAUCUAUUGAGUCCCUUUCUCCAGGGGGUGAUUUAUUUGGAUUGGGCAUCUUUAAAAAUGGCAGUGACAGCCUCCAGCGAAGCACUUCUUUAGAAAGUUGGUUGACUUCCUAUAAAAGCAAUGAAGAUCUCUUUAGCUGUCACAGCUCUGGGGAUAUAAGCGUGAGCAGUGGCUCAGUUGGUGAACUAAGUAAAAGAACAUUAGAUCUCCUGAAUCGUUUGGAGAAUAUCCAGAGCCCCUCAGAGCAAAAGAUAAAACGAAGUGUUUCUGAUAUCACUCUUCAAAGCAGUUCCCAAAAGAUGUCCUUUACUGGCCAGAUGUCAUUGGACAUAGCAUCUUCUAUCAAUGAAGACUCAGCGGCAUCUCUAACAGAACUUAGCAGCAGUGACGAGCUCUCUCUUUGCUCAGAGGAUAUUGUGUUACACAAGAACAAGAUCCCGGAAUCGAAUGCAUCGUUCAGGAAGCGUCUGACUCGUUCAGUGGCUGAUGAAAGCGAUGUCAAUGUCAGCAUGAUUGUUAAUGUCUCUUGCACCUCUGCUUGCACUGAUGAUGAAGAUGACAGCGACCUGCUCUCCAGCUCUACCCUUACCUUGACUGAAGAAGAGCUGUGCAUCAAAGAUGAGGAUGACGACUCCAGUAUUGCAACAGAUGAUGAAAUUUAUGAAGACUGCACCUUGAUGUCAGGGCUAGACUACAUAAAGAAUGAAUUACAGACCUGGAUUAGGCCAAAAUUGUCUUUGACAAGAGAUAAGAAAAGGUGCAAUGUCAGUGAUGAGAUGAAGGGCAGUAAAGAUAUAAGUAGCAGUGAGAUGACCAAUCCCUCUGAUACUCUGAAUAUUGAGACCCUUCUAAAUGGCUCUGUAAAACGUGUCUCUGAAAAUAAUGGAAAUGGUAAGAAUUCAUCUCAUACCCAUGAGUUAGGGACAAAGCGUGAAAAUAAGAAAACUAUUUUCAAAGUUAAUAAAGAUCCAUAUGUGGCUGACAUGGAAAAUGGCAAUAUUGAAGGUAUUCCAGAAAGGCAAAAGGGAAAACCGAAUGUGACUUCAAAGGUAUCAGAAAAUCUUGGUUCACAUGGGAAAGAGAUUUCAGAGAGUGAGCAUUGUAAGUGUAAAGCACUUAUGGAUAGUUUAGAUGAUUCAAAUACUGCUGGCAAGGAAUUUGUUUCCCAAGAUGUUAGACAUCUUCCAAAGAAAUGUCCAAAUCACCACCAUUUUGAAAAUCAAAGCACUGCCUCUACUCCCACUGAGAAGUCUUUCUCAGAACUGGCUUUAGAAACCAGGUUUAACAACAGACAAGACUCUGAUGCACUGAAAUCAUCUGAUGAUGCACCGAGUAUGGCUGGAAAAUCUGCUGGUUGUUGCCUAGCACUUGAACAAAACGGAACAGAGGAAAAUGCUUCUAUCAGCAACAUUUCCUGUUGCAACUGUGAGCCAGAUGUUUUCCAUCAAAAAGAUGCCGAAGAUUGUUCAGUACACAACUUUGUUAAGGAAAUCAUUGACAUGGCUUCGACAGCCCUAAAAAGUAAAUCUCAACCUGAAAACGAGGUGGCUGCUCCUACUUCAUUAACUCAAAUCAAGGAGAAAGUGUUGGAGCAUUCUCACCGGCCCAUCCAGCUGAGAAAAGGGGACUUUUAUUCGUACUUAUCUCUCUCAUCUCAUGACAGUGAUUGUGGGGAGGUCACCAAUUACAUAGAAGAGAAAAGCAGCACUCCAUUGCCACUAGACACCACUGACUCGGGCUUAGAUGACAAGGAAGAUAUUGAAUGCUUUUUUGAGGCCUGUGUUGAGGGUGACUCUGAUGGAGAGGAGCCUUGUUUCUCUAGUGCUCCUCCAAAUGAAUCUGCAGUUCCCAGCGAAGCUGCAAUGCCACUACAAGCAACAGCAUGUUCUUCUGAGUUCAGUGAUAGUUCUCUUUCAGCUGAUGAUGCAGAUACAGUGGCUCUUUCAAGUCCUUCCUCUCAGGAAAGAGCUGAGGUUGGAAAGGAAGUGAAUGGUUUGCCCCAAACUUCCAGUGGCUGUGCAGAAAACUUAGAGUUUACUCCUUCAAAGCUUGACAGUGAAAAGGAAAGUUCCGGAAAACCAGGUGAAUCUGGAAUGCCAGAAGAACAUAAUGCUGCUUCAGCCAAAUCUAAAGUUCAAGACCUCUCCUUGAAGGCAAAUCAGCCAACAGACAAGGCCGCAUUGCAUCCCAGCCCCAAAACUUUAACCUGUGAAGAAAAUCUUCUAAACCUUCAUGAAAAACGACAUAGAAAUAUGCAUAGGUAGAAUGUACCCCCUCCCCAAGCAUGAAAAUCAUCUCACUGAAAGAUACGCCUGGCUGCAACUCAGGGGUGGCCUCAUCCUCCCGCCCUGGGCUGGCCUCUGGUUCCAUCACGUUUGUCACUGCCGUUUAUUACAUUGACUUCUCCCAAGAUGAAUCUUCCUUCCAAAUGUGUUUUCUCCACACAAGCCUUGUGAUCUGAAUGUGUGCGCUGGUUCUCUUUAGGUGAUCGUCUUUGAAGUUCAGCAAAGCUGCUUGUUCUCCCAUGGAUUCCUGUCCCAAGCUACCUCUACCAACCCUCUCUCUCCAGCUAGACUUUUCUCUUUGCCUCCUCCCUUCCCUUCCACUCUUUAAAGUUCUGCAGUUCACCAACUGGUAGUCCAUUAAAUUCUCCUGUCUAGAAUGACCCCCCCACCAGUACUUGACCAAUUUCAUGUAUCAAUCUGGAUUUUUUUUUAACGGUAUAAUGACUGUGUUUAUUGAAAGAGUUUUACCUAAAAAGCCAACAUUUGAAUUGGUUGCAGCAUAGAGAAGAAACACUGGUCCUUCUUUCAAAAUUAAGCAACUAUUAAAAGCGCCAUUUUAUUUAUUUCAUUUAAAAAAUAAUCUAUGCAGCAUUUCAAGAAACAACCAUAUGGUGUUGUAUAUUAUAAACUGGUGACAUUCUACUAUUGAAUUAUGUACAACAUUUUCAUUUUUUAUGCUUCUUGAGGUGGUAAUGAGAAAAAAGUUUUUUAAAAAAGUGUGCCUUGCUGUAUUUCUUAUACCAUUUAUUAAAAAGCUGCUUUCACGGUAAAAUUAUGUUGGUUUGAAAGGAGGAAAUAGCAAGGUUAAGAUGUGUGAAUAAUUUCUGUAUAUAUGUAUAACCAAGUACAAACAUUGAUGUAUAAUGACAGUAUAAAAUGCUUUCAUGUUUGUGAUGUCUAGUGAUGUGGAAAAUAUAAGCCUUAAAUCCAUUAGAUUGCAUGGUAAUUAAAAUUGGCAUAAUAAACACAGAUUAUUGGGGGAAAAGGAAAAUUAGUGAUCUCUUCUACUAUGUUCUUUACCAAAUUGUUGCAUCUGGUUCUGAAAAAGUAUAGCAUGUAGCAGCUUCCAAACAUAUUCAUAUUGCUUAAGAGGCUUAACAUUACCUAAACUAGAGACUAGACGUAAAGCCUUCAGUUUUCAAAAUCUUUCUGGUCACUAUAAAGAUCUUGGAACAGCAAAUGAUUAAAUGUCAGUUCCCCUAAACCAAUAAACAUUUAUACUAGAUUUUUUAUUUCCACUUAUCAUUAAUGAUUUAAUGUUGGAUUUCAGGUACCUUGUAUGUCUUAAUUUAUUUUAAAUAUUUAUUUUGAAUGAGUUUGAUAGAAAGCUAGUAGAAAAGUACAGAAAAUUUGACUAUUAUUUAUAGAUUUCAGGUAUAUUUAUAUGUGUAAAAGAAAUUGACAAAGAAAUAUUUCAUCUGGCCUUUACUGACUCCUGUUAAAUGCAGUUUUAAAUUUAUAUCGUAACACCUACUUAAGUGCCUGACACAGUAGGUAUUCAAUAAAAAUUUACUGAAUUAAAGGAUUAAAUUAGGUGACAUGGUGACAUCUAUCCCUUUAUUUUGACACUAAAACAUGGACACAACUAGAAAGAGGUACAAUGCAAUAUAAAGUCACAAUAGAUAAUAUAUAUCAAAUUUCUAAAAGGUAAAGAAUGUUGUGGGUUCAUGCAGUCACAGGAAUGACAAUCAUUCAACAGAUAGUUCAGAAACACUUUUUAUCUGCAAGGCACUAUUCUAGAUCCAGAAGAUGCAAUGUUGAACAAACAGACAAAGCCCUGCCCUCAGAAGGCUGUCCUGCAUUAGGAACAAGUGAACACGCAAAUGACAUGAAGUAUUUGUUGCAGAGCUGAGGAACAGAGCAAAUGUAGUGAUAGAAGCGCAAUGAGAGAAGCAGCAGUGGGUACAAGGAGGAAGAAAAAGGGCUUGCAGAGAGUGGAAAGUUAGUGGAAUAUUCAUGAAACUUCAUUGCAGGGGUAAUAGAAGAAAAAGUAAAUUGGGAGGACUUAAUGGAAGGUCUUUUAAAAAGUUAACUUGGAGCUUCUGUAUGUAAAAUGCUAGGUAAUAAGGACACUUUGUACAGGCUGUUUUGCACCUGAUUUUAUUUAUCAUUAGUGCCACGCCAAGAUCAUUUAGACGAUGCUUAUCUGUAAUUCUACCACUUUAAUAACUAUUUGUAUUUUUAUGCCCCUUCUGAUCUUUUCCAUAUGUAUUUCUAAAUGGAUAAAUUAUUCUAGGCUUCUUAAUAGGUAGUAAUUUGUUCAAAAGCGGUUUUAGCCAGACAUCUAGUUGCAGUGUUCAAGAGGAUUAUGGGGGAAAGAGAUUAGAGAUAAUUGUCUAGUUAGGGGGCAGCUGGAGAAAAUAAGCUAAGUUUGCAAUAACAGAGUACACAAGUAUAGUGGCCCAGGAUGUAGUGAAAGAACAAAUCCUAGAGUCUUUGAAAUUUCUAAGGGCAUUCUAGACCUCUGUUGGGAUAUGGUAUUAUUUUACAUACUGACACAACCUAAAUUUUCUUUGGGUAGUAACUAAUGUCAAGUCUACAUCGACUGGUAAAACAUUCAAAGAACAAACUGACAAUGAUGUUCUACCUACUUGUUACAUGCUCAUGGAAGACCGUGCAGUAUUGAAAGUAUUUGUUAAUUAUCUGCUUAGUAUUAACACUAAAUUUGUAGAAUGACUUUCAGGUUUGUUGAACAAUGCCUUUUCAGGUUGGAAGAAGAAAAAUAGCCUCAAUCUCCCACCCCAUGUAGGCACUACCUCCCCAAUUACCCUUAGAAAAUGAUCACACCAACUCUGCCUACACACUUCCAGUGAUAGUGGCUCAUUGUCUGUUAAGGCAAACUGUUCCACUGUUGGGCAUAUCUCUUUGUUAGAAAGUUCUUUCUUAGGUUGCUAAAAUCUGCCUAGUACCCCGCUACCCUGUUCUGUCUUAUGGAGCAGCCCAGAUUAUCUUUACUCCCUCUUUCUCAUGGCAACCCUGAAGAUAAUCAAGGCCAGUUACUCAUCAUCUCCCAACCACUGUUUCCUCAACUGCCCUUCAUAUGUCAUGGUUUUCAGAUCCAUUCCAACCUGACUGAAUGUUAACAGACAGAAUUCUUCACAUUAAGGAACUGUCUUCAUCAUCAUACAUGUAGAAAAGAAUCUGAACAUUUAAGUGCGAAGUUUUCUCUAGAAAUAUAUUCAAGAUAUGUUUAUUCUAUUAUUGUAAAUUUCAAACAAUAAAUAAAUAAGAAUCCAUGACUUCCUUCAGUGGCCCAGUCCAGUGCCUAAGUCAUCUGGAAUCUUCUCCUUACAUCGAAUACAAACCUAACCUGUUUCCAAGUAGGGCACUCCCUCCGCUUAUUUAUUCAUUUAUUCAGCCAUUCAGCAAACAUUUAUUAAAUGGCUACCUAUGUGAGGCACUAUAUUUGGCAUUAGGUAUAUAAAGGCAACUAACACAUGGUAUCUGUCUCCAAAGGUUUACAGCUUUUCUUCUGAAAGUGCCUUUUGUGUCCUUGAAUAGAGUGAUUAUGACUUUUGUCUCAAUUAAAUGAUGACCUCAUUUAGUUUCUGAUGAAGUUUCUCUACAUUUAAGAAAAUCUAGUGAGCAAAACGGUAUACAAAAAAUCAUCUGGAUCUGACUACCAGAAAAAGUAAAGUGGUUUUAAUUACAGAAAGAAAAAUAUUUGUUAGAUUUCUGGUCACUGAAUAAAUAUGCAUCUUAUACAACACAGAACAACCUAAAUUUAGGGCUUCUGGAAACCUGAGUUUGAUGACUUUGUUGUGUUUGGUUCAUCCGGACUAGGUUUCACCCAUUCUAUAAUUCCUAGAAACAAACUAGAUGAAAAUAUCAAUGAAAUGAUCCAGGUCUGUCUUACAAGUCAAUUUGCUUUAGCUUCCAAAAGAAGUUGAAAUUUUUUAGAAUUUUAAAGAAAAACUCACUUUUCAAGUGUCAUAUAAUUCUUAUAUUUUAAAUAUAAAUCGAACCAACUAAAUUUACCGCUAUAUUUUUUUCUACAUAUUCUUUUUUCAAUUUUCAUUUUGAAAAAAUUCAGACCUAUGUAAAAGUUGAGAGUAGAACAAAGAUACUUGGUACUCAUCCCUCAGGUUCAUUUAUUGUUAAUAUUUCACCAUAUUUACUUCAUCUCUGUAUACACACACACUUUUUUGUAUGAUUAAAUCAUUUGAAAUUAAAUUGUAGAGUAUGAUACUUCAUCUGCAAAUACUUCAGCAUGUGUUAGCUGAGAACAUGGGUAUUCUUCUGCAAGUCUACAAUACCAUCUUCAUACUCAAGAAAUGUAACAUUGGCUGGUCAUGGUGGCUCACGCCUGUAAUCCCAGCACUUUGGGAGGCCAAGGCGUGUGGAUCACCUAAGGUCAGGAGUUCGAGAUCAGCCUGGCCAACAUGGUGAAACCCCGUCUCUACUAAAAAUACAAAAAUUAGCCAGGCGUGGUAGCUGUAAUCCCAGCUACUUGGGAGGCUGAGGCAGGAGAAUUGCUUGAAGCCAGGAGGCAGAGGUUGCAGUGAGCCGAGAUUGCACCACUGCACUCCAGCCUGGGCAAGAAGAGUGAAAUUUUGUCUCAAAAAAAAAAAUGUAAUAUUAAUACAAUAAUACCUGAUAGUUUAUAUUCAAGUUUCUCUAACUACCCAAAUUAUGUCCUCUUAUAGUUGUUUUUGUUUUAAUACAGUAUUCAAACAAAGAUCACACACUGCUUUUAGUUUCCAAGUCUUUUUUUUUUUUUUUUUUUUUAAAUCUUGCAUAGUUUCCCUGUGCUUUUACUCUAUUUUUCUUUGGGCUUUUAUAACAUCGACAGUUCUGAAAAGUCCAGGCCAGUUUUGCAGAAUGAUCCACAAUCUUGAUGGGUCUAGUUGUUUUCUCAUUGUUAAACUCAGGGUAAACUUUUUUUUGUCAAGUAAAUACAUAGGUGACUUUGCAUUCACAGCCACUCUUUAAUGAAGAUUGAUUGAAUAACUGACAUUCCUGAUAUGUUUUAAAGUUCACAGCUUACUCUUUCAGCCCAUGCUUCAUCCAUCUAAGGCAAGGGUCAGCAAACUGUGGCACGUGGGCCAAAUUCAGCUCGUUGCCUGUUCUGGUUUGACCCAUUUGAACAAUUGACGAGCUUCAAACAAUUUUUACAUUUUUUAGUAGUUAAACAAAAGAAUACUUCAUGACAUGUGAAAAUCAUAUGAAAUUUAAAUUUUGGUGUCCAUGUAUAAAGUUUUAUUAGAACACAUCCACGCACAUUUGUUUCCAUAGUCUACGGAUGCUUUGACACUAUACAAAGUUACGUACUUGCAACAAAAGCCAUAUGGCCUGCAAAACCUAAAACAUUUACUAUCUGGAUCAUUACAGAAAGUUUUCUGAUCCCUGGUCUAUGAUAUUCUAAAUUCCGACACAUUUUCUUAGGAUAGAUUUCCAUUUGCAAAUUCAGUGUAAGACAUAAACACCGGCAAUAGUUGUGUUUUUUUUUUCUUUUUACUUCCUAGAUUUUAUUGCAUUCUCAACUUGUUUCAUAUUACCUUAAAAAAUAAAGUGCACUUAAAGAUUGUUUCACAUCCACAGUUUGUUUAAGGAUUUAAAUUUAGUUCACUAUUACUGCCUGGCUUUGAUUGAUUUAGAGGGUUAGUCAAUUACAGACUAAAUAAUUAGUUCAAUCAAAACCAUCAGAAAAAUUGACACAAACUCACUUCCAUGCACCAGUAAACUGGAAUCCUUUCUUUAAAUGUUUUUCUAAAGCAAUCCGAGGAAUUAAAUUCAGGCCAUUUCACAGUCAGUUUUUUUCAAAUUCAUUUUUCAACUCAAAGGCAAAACCAUGAUCAAAAUAUUGUAUAUAGUACACCUUCAGUUCCCAACUGCUGAAUUUACCAAGGAAUUAAGUAUUCACCACAAACCCUGGUGUGGCCAUAGGUGGACACUCUAAUUAAAAAGAAGAUGUUCAAAAAGAAUAGUCCUUCUUUUCUUUCUUAAAUUCACCUUUGAUAGCACUGCCACACUUCUGGGAAGGGAACGUUCAAGGAAACCGUAUAGCCACUUCUUUUUUAAAAGCAGCCACAUACCUUCUAUAUAACAAUGGCCCUUUAGUUUGAGAGUUGCCACAUAUUUGCAUUUCCAGAGUAAAAUAAUAGGAUGACAUGGGCAGGUCAGGCCCACAAUAGUAUGGUUUCUUUGGCAAAGGCAUUUUGGCCAAUGCCGUAAGACCAUUCUGGCCCUUGAUUAAUGGGUUCUCACCAAAGCAGAAAUUACGCAGAGCUUAUUUGUCCUUGCAUUUUGAAGUAAAUCAUUGCCUGCAUAAAGCAACUCUUUUGUCUCUUUUCCAUUGCAACACACAGGAGUUGGAAUGUGUUCAUACGUGUAAGACUGUCUUAGUCUGCCCAGACUGCUUGGACUGUGUUGUUUAUAAACAACAGAAUUUACUGCUCAAAGUUCUGGAGACUGGGAAGUUCAAGAUCAAGAUGCUAGCAGAUUCAGUGUCUGAGGAGGGCUCACUUUCUGUUUCAUUGAUGCACCUUACUGCAUCCUCAUCUGGUGGAAGGGGCAGUGAACAAGCUCCCUUGGGCCCCUUUUACGAAAGCACUAAUUCCAUUCAUGAAGACUUCACAACUUAAUCACCUCCCAAAGGCUCCAUCUCUUAAUACGAUCACAUUGGGGAUUAGGUUUCAACAUACCAAUUUUGGGGGUACACAAAUAUUGAGGUGAUAGACACUUCCAGGCUUUUGCCAAACAUUAGUAAACAAUUUCCAGUGAAUACUCUGCCCCAUUCUCUCCUACUCAAGCAGAGUAUCUUAAGGCAGCAGAUUGGAGUGACGUUACUUUAAGGGUAACUUUGAAGCCAAUCUAAUUCAUACUCAAAAAAGUAUUCCAAAAUUUUGGUACUCUAUUAUGGGUUACAAACCCCUUGUGACACCAUAUUUAAGAGCCACUGCUAUUGAGGCUUGCACUCUCUUGCUUGAAAUGAGGUGCUCCCAAACCUGGGAGAUGGCUCCCAAAGAACAAGAGAAUCAACCCCAUCGUGCAUUUAUGUGCUGCCCCAGGUAAUCCACAGGCACAAAGAACUUGAGCUUCCUGGUGUGUUCUUCAGAAAAAAAGGAAUUCAAAAAGCAAAUGUAAAAUGGAACAGAACUUGGCCUCAAAGUGAUGUUGGAAAAAUAGCCAGUCCUGAUGACUUGGUCGAGGUAACUUGCUUUGCCCACUGUUAACUACAGAGCCAUAUGAUAAUGGAACAUCAAGGUUUUCCAGAUAAACCCAAAGCCUUUUGUGUCUAUACCUUGUAACCUGUCAUGUUCAUCAACGUUUUAGACUGUACCAUUGCUCUUUCUCCCUUCUUUAUUCAUUUUAUAUGGGGACGUUUGACUAGGAUCACCAGAUGUAGAUUUGGUAAUUUUUCCAUACCAUUAAGAUGUAUGAUAAUGGAUUUUAUUAAUUUAACACAAAUGCAUAAAAAUAUGAUGUAAUAAGAAACAAUCCUGAAAUUAUUAAAACAUUUCUUUGUCCUUACUUAAACCUAACCUGCCAUUUUAAAAGACACCUAACUCUAUAAACAAAUGGGCCAUUACAGACGUAAAACAAAUAUUAUUCAGUGAAAUUUAUUCAAGGACUUAAAAUGAUUGAAGGCAUUAGGAACAUAAAAAUGCAUAAGAUCCUCUUUUAAAUCCCAAUAUUCCCUAACCACUGGUUUAUAAAAAAUACUCUAAGGUUUAUAGAAUUAGUUUGGUUCCGUUAGUUGAUCAAGUUACUUACACUAAGUCAGCAAUUCAAAACAAAUAAUUCCCUCUGUGUGUGUUUGUUUGCUUGCAAAUAUGUUUCAUUUUAAAGUGUCUUUUUAUAUAGAAAGCCAAGUUGGUGGAAUUUAUCUUGUCAUUAAAAUGAUGUGAAAAUCAAA